UUGGCAUAUUUGCAUUUUUAAUAGUCCCUGAGGAGUUCAGGAGGAAACAGGGUUUUACAUCCCCUUUUAGGGACGCAAGUAGGAUUGCCCCAAAAAGUUCCACUCCGUUCACACUCAGCGAGGGCCCGGCAAGAGCCCCACCUUUCACAUUCAUUAUUUCCCUUACUAACCGAGGCUCCGAGACGCUAAACAAGCAGCCCAAGGUCACACCGCAGAGUGAGGGCAGCAGAGCCUCUGCGCCUGCCUCCUCCCUUCGGACCCUGCCGCGUUCCCAGAGGCUGGACUCAGCAAGCUGGAACAGGAAUCGAACCCUCAGGCCCUCGUCGCCGUCCCAGCCCUCGAGGAAUCUGCGCCCCAGGCGAAGCUGUCCUCGGAGGCCCAGAGGCCUUUGGGCCAAAGGCAGCCCCGCCGGUCCUUCUUUGAAUCCUUCAUCCGGACCCUCAUCAUCACGUGUGUGGCCCUGGCUGUGGUCCUGUCCUCGGUCUCCAUUUGUGAUGGGCACUGGCUCCUGGCUGAGGACCGCCUCUUCGGGCUCUGGCACUUCUGCACCACCACCAACCAGACGAUCUGCUUCAGAGACCUGGGCCAGGCCCAUGUGCCCGGGCUGGCCGUGGGCAUGGGCCUGGUACGCAGCGUGGGCGCCUUGGCCGUGGUGGCCGCCAUUUUUGGCCUGGAGUUCCUCAUGGUGUCCCAGUUGUGCGAGGACAAACACUCACAGUGCAAGUGGGUCAUGGGUUCCAUCCUCCUCCUGGUGUCUUUCGUCCUCUCCUCCGGCGGGCUCCUGGGUUUUGUGAUCCUCCUCAGGAACCAAGUCACACUCAUCGGCUUCACCCUAAUGUUUUGGUGCGAAUUCACUGCCUCCUUCCUCCUCUUCCUGAACGCCAUCAGCGGCCUUCACAUCAACAGCAUCACCCAUCCCUGGGAAUGACCGUGGAAAUUUUAGGCCCCCUCCAGGGACAUCAGAUUCCACAAGAAAAUAUGGUCAAAAUGGGACUUUUCCAGCAUGUGGCCUCUGGUGGGGCUGGGUUGGACAAGGGCCUUGAAACGGCUGCCUGUUUGCCGAUAACUUGUGGGUGGUCAGCCAGAAAUGGCCCGGGGGCCUCUGCACCUGGUCUGCAGGGCCAGAGGCCAGGAGGGUGCCUCAGUGCCACCAACUGCACAGGCUUAGCCAGAUGUUGAUUUUAGAGGAAGAAAAAAACAUUUUAAAACUCCUUCUUGAAUUUUCUUCCCUGGACUGGAAUACAGUUGGAAGCACAGGGGUAACUGGUACCUGAGCUAGCUGCACAGCCAAGGAUAGUUCAUGCCUGUUUCAUUGACACGUGCUGGGAUAGGGGCUGCAGAAUCCCUGGGGCUCCCAGGGUUGUUAAGAAUGGAUCAUUCUUCCAGCUAAGGGUCCAAUCAGUGCCUAGGACUUUCUUCCACCAGCUCAAAGGGCCUUCGUAUGUAUGUCCCUGGCUUCAGCUUUGGUCAUGCCAAAGAGGCAGAGUUCAGGAUUCCCUCAGAAUGCCCUGCACACAGUAGGUUUCCAAACCAUUUGACUCGGUUUGCCUCCCUGCCCGUUGUUUAAACCUUACAAACCCUGGAUAACCCCAUCUUCUAGCAGCUGGCUGUGCCUCUGGGAGCUCUGCCUAUCAGAACCCUACCUUAAGGUGGGUUUCCUUCCGAGAAGAGUUCUUGAGCAAGCUCUCCCAGGAGGGCCCACCUGACUGCUAAUACACAGCCCUCCCCAAGGCCCGUGUGUGCAUGUGUCUGUCUUUUGUGAGGGUUAGACAGCCUCAGGGCACCAUUUUUAAUCCCAGAACACAUUUCAAAGAGCACGUAUCUAGACCUGCUGGACUCUGCAGGGGGUGAGGGGGAACAGCGAGAGCUUGGGUAAUGAUUAACACCCAUGCUGGGGAUGCAUGGAGGUGAAGGGGGCCAGGAACCAGUGGAGAUUUCCAUCCUUGCCAGCACGUCUGUACUUCUGUUCAUUAAAGUGCUCCCUUUCUAGUC